GCCCCGCAGAGGACUUGCCUCCACCGCCACCUGCAAGUCCGCCCAGCUGUACUUCUGCGCAGGCUCCAGGAGUUGUUUGCUGUCUCUAUGGCAACCCAGUAGCUGGAGUCUGAAGAUGGAGACCAACGAGUCUACGGAGGGAUCGCGGUCGCGGUCGCGAUCUUUAGACAUACAGCCCAGCUCCGAAGGACUGGGGCCCACUUCGGAACCGUUUCCUUCUUCAGAUGACAGUCCCAGGUCGGCCCUGGCAGCUGCAACCGCAGCAGCUGCAGCGGCUGCAUCAGCUGCUGCAGCUACUGCAGCCUUCACCACUGCCAAAGCAGCUGCAUUAUCUACAAAGACCCCAGCGCCCUGUUCUGAGUUCAUGGAGCCGUCCUCUGACCCCAGCCUUCUUGGGGAGCCCUGUGCGGGACCCGGCUUUACCCACAAUAUAGCCCAUGGGAGUCUUGGCUUUGAGCCCGUCUAUGUUUCCUGUAUUGCUCAGGACACUUGCACUACAACUGACCAUAGUUCUAAUCCUGGCCCUGUUCCAGGCUCUAGCUCUGGGCCUGUUCUUGGUUCCAGCUCAGGUGCUGGCCAUGGCUCUGGCUCUGGCUCUGGUCCUGGCUGUGGCUCUGUCCCUGGCUCUGGCUCUGGUCCUGGUCCUGGCUCUGGUCCUGGCUCUGGUCCUGGUCAUGGCUCUGGCUCUCAUCCUGGUCCUGCCUCUGGGCCUGGUCCAGACACUGGCCCUGACUCUGAGCUCAGCCCCUGUAUUCCUCCAGGGUUCAGAAACCUGGUGGCAGAUCGGGUCCCUAACUAUACCUCCUGGAGUCAGCACUGCCCCUGGGAGCCCCAGAAACAACCACCUUGGGAAUUUUUGCAAGUCUUAGAACCGGGUGCCCGAGGACUAUGGAAACCCCCAGACAUUAAAGGGAAGCUUAUGGUUUGCUAUGAAACUUUGCCGCGGGGCCAGUGCCUCCUCUACAACUGGGAGGAAGAGAGAGCCACCAACCACCUGGAUCAAGUCCCAAGCAUGCAGGAUGGCUCUGAGAGUUUUUUCUUCCGACACGGACACCGGGGACUGCUGACUAUGCAACUAAAGUCACCCAUGCCCUCCAGCACCACCCAGAAAGACUCGUACCAGCCACCAGGAAACGUCUAUUGGCCACUUCGAGGGAAGCGUGAAGCCAUGCUGGAGAUGCUCCUGCAGCAUCAGAUCUGUAAAGAGGUGCAGGCAGAACAGGAACCCACAAGGAAGCUCUUCGAGGUUGAGUCUGUGACACACCAUGACUACCGAAUGGAGCUGGCACAAGCAGGGACUCCUGCCCCAACAAAGCCUCACGACUACCGCCAGGAGCAACCUGAGACCUUCUGGAUACAGAGGGCACCACAGCUGCCGACAUGGUGGCCAUUGCCCACCCAGGUACCAGCAGCAGAAGACUAUCUGACUUGGAAAGAAUGGGGGUUUACAGGAGUCCAGGAGGUCCUUUCCGCUCUCCUAAGAGCCACACCUGGUGAAUACUCAGUAAACAUUUGCGGAAUGAAUGAACACCCUGUCUGCAGCAGGACAUGGACAAAUAGGCUCUGCCAUCAGGAAAUGGGAAGCAAGAAAACGGUAACUCAAGAGGACAGAGGCUGGUGAGGAGGUAAAGCAGGCCCAGUGAAAUGGACCUGACAGCCCAAACUGUCAGAGAGGAGGAAAGCAGGCAUUUGAUUUUGGUAAUUGUGCCAAAGCUAUGUAAGAGAAUAAAUGCCAUUGUUUUAAGGAAAUACACAGUGAAGUUUUUAGGAAAUACACACUAAGUAUUUAGGGAUAAAGUAGUUAUCCCUAAAUAGUAGUCUGCCACAUGCCAAACAAUGUUAGGUACUUUCCAUACAACGAAUCUAUUAUUCCCAUCUUACAGAUAAAACAACUGAGGCUCAGGGAGAUUCUGUGACUUACCUAAGGCCACACAGUUAGCAACAAGCCAAUAUUCAAAUCCAGAUGAUUUUUACUCCCAAGGACAAUAAAUCCAACUCAAUAACUUCAA